ACAUUGGCAGGUAACGAGCGGCGGCGGCGGCAGCGGGUCUUGGGUCCUCCGAGAGCAGCAGCGAUUUUCUAUUUUGUACAUACAUUAUUUUGUAUAUACUGUAUAUGAUGACUUCAGUGAGCAGUGACCAUUGUCGAGGUGCUCGGGAAAAACCACAGAUUUCAGCAGCACAAUCAACGCAACCACAGAAACAAGUGGUACAGCUGUACCGACCUCUUGACACUUCCUAGAGCUCAGCCUGGCAACAGCUGAACAGAUGCGUCUCGCUCAAGUGAUCUUUGAUAAGAAUGAUUCAGAUUUUGAAGCUAAAGUUAAGCAGCUUAUGGAAGUGACAGGGAAAAAUCAGGAUGAAUGCAUAGUGGCCCUACAUGAUUGUAAUGGAGAUGUGAACAAAGCUAUCAAUAUAUUGCUGGAAGGGAAUUCAGACACAACUUCAUGGGAGACUGUAGGGUGUAAGAAAAAGAAUUUUGCAAAAGAAAAUUCAGAAAACAAAGAGAAUAGAGAGAAGAAAAGCGAGAAAGAAUCGAGUCGUGGACGUGGAAACAACAACCGGAAAGGAAGAGGCGGCAAUCGUGGCAGAGAAUUUAGAGGUGAAGAAAAUGGAAUUGAUUGCAAUCAAGUGGACAAACCUUCAGAUCGUGGCAAGCGAGCCCGGGGUAGAGGAUUUGGACGUGGCAGAGGGAGAGGGGCAGGAAGGUUCUCAACCCAAGGCAUGGGGACAUUUAAUCCUGCAGACUAUUCAGAUUCUACAUCUACAGAUGUGUGUGGGACAAAGCUAGUAGUUUGGGAAGCUGCUCAGAAUGGUGCAGAUGAGGGAACUGAACUGGCAUCAAAUACUCACAACAUAGCUCAGGAUCUGUCAAACAAAAGUUCUUAUGGACUCAAAGGGGCUUGGAAGAAUUCUGUGGAAGAGUGGACAACAGAAGACUGGACUGAAGAUCUUUCUGAAACAAAGGUCUUCACUGCCUCAUCUGCUCCAGCAGAGAAUCACAUCUUACCUGGGCAAAGCAUUGAUCUGGUAGCCUUGCUCCAGAAGCCUGUUCCUCACAGUCAAGCCUCAGAAGCCAACUCCUUUGAAACUUCCCAACAGCAGGGCUUUGGCCAAGCCCUUGUCUUCACAAAUUCGCAACACAACAAUCAGAUGGCACCAGGGACUGGCAGCUCCACUGCCGUCAACUCCUGUUCUCCUCAGAGCCUGUCAUCCGUCCUUGGCUCAGGAUUUGGAGAGCUUGCACCACCAAAAAUGGCAAACAUCACCAGCUCCCAGAUUUUGGACCAGUUGAAAGCUCCGAGUUUGGGCCAGUUUACCACCACCCCAAGUACACAGCAGAAUAGUACAAGUCACCCUACAACUACUACUUCUUGGGACCUCAAGCCCCCAACAUCCCAGUCCUCAGUCCUCAGUCAUCUUGACUUCAAAUCUCAACCUGAGCCAUCCCCAGUUCUUAGCCAGUUGAGCCAGCGACAACAGCACCAGAGCCAGGCAGUCACUGUUCCUCCUCCUGGUUUGGAGUCCUUUCCUUCCCAGGCAAAACUUCGAGAAUCAACACCUGGAGACAGUCCCUCCACUGUGAACAAGCUUUUGCAGCUUCCCAGCACGACCAUUGAAAAUAUCUCUGUGUCUGUCCACCAGCCACAGCCCAAACACAUCAAACUUGCUAAGCGGCGGAUACCCCCAGCUUCUAAGAUCCCAGCUUCUGCAGUGGAAAUGCCUGGUUCAGCAGAUGUCACAGGAUUAAAUGUGCAGUUUGGGGCUCUGGAAUUUGGGUCAGAACCUUCUCUCUCUGAAUUUGGAUCAGCUCCAAGCAGUGAAAAUAGUAAUCAGAUUCCCAUCAGCUUGUAUUCGAAGUCUUUAAGUGAGCCUUUGAAUACAUCUUUAUCAAUGACCAGUGCAGUACAGAACUCCACAUAUACAACUUCCGUCAUUACCUCCUGCAGUCUGACAAGCUCAUCACUGAAUUCUGCUAGUCCAGUAGCAAUGUCUUCCUCUUAUGACCAGAGUUCUGUGCAUAACAGGAUCCCAUACCAAAGCCCUGUGAGUUCAUCAGAGUCAGCUCCAGGAACCAUCAUGAAUGGACAUGGUGGUGGUCGAAGUCAGCAGACACUAGACACUCCAAAGACAACAGGCCCUCCCUCUGCCCUCCCGUCUGUGAGCUCCCUGCCCAGCACCACCUCCUGCACUGCACUUCUGCCGUCCACAUCCCAGCACACUGGCGACCUGACUAGCAGCCCUCUCUCUCAGCUUAGCAGUUCGCUCUCCAGCCACCAGAGCAGCCUCUCUGCACAUGCAGCCCUCUCCUCGAGCACGUCACACACACAUGCCAGUGUGGAGAGCGCCUCUUCCCACCAGUCCUCAGCCACCUUCUCCACGGCAGCGACCUCCGUCUCAAGUUCCGCAUCCUCAGGCGCCAGCCUGUCCAGUAGCAUGAACACCGCGAACAGCCUCUGUCUGGGUGGGACCCCCGCGAGUGCAUCCAGCAGCAGUAGCAGGGCCGCGCCCUUGGUGACCUCAGGCAAAGCACCCCCAAACUUACCUCAGGGGGUGCCUCCCCUGCUGCACAACCAGUACCUCGUAGGUCCCGGAGGACUGCUUCCUGCCUACCCGAUCUAUGGCUAUGACGAGCUCCAGAUGCUGCAGUCACGGCUGCCAGUGGACUACUAUGGAAUUCCCUUUGCUGCACCCACAGCGCUUGCCAGCCGAGAUGGGAGCCUAGCUAAUAAUCCAUAUCCAGGUGAUGUCACAAAGUUUGGCCGUGGGGACUCUGCAUCCCCUGCACCCGCUACCACACCAGCUCAGCCACAGCAGAGCCAAUCACAGACCCACCACACAGCCCAGCAGCCCUUCGUGAAUCCUGCACUGCCACCUGGCUAUAGCUACACUGGUCUUCCCUACUACACAGGCAUGCCCAGUGCCUUCCAGUAUGGCCCCACCAUGUUUGUCCCUCCAGCCUCAGCCAAGCAACAUGGGGUGAACCUCAGCACUCCCACACCUCCCUUCCAGCAGGCCAGUGGUUAUGGCCAGCACGGCUACAGUACAGGUUAUGACGACCUGACCCAGGGGACAGCAGCAGGAGACUACUCCAAAGGUGGCUAUGCUGGAUCAUCGCAGGCACCAAACAAGUCUGCAGGUUCUGGGCCUGGCAAAGGAGUAUCAGUGUCUUCAAGCACCACUGGUCUACCUGAUAUGACUGGUUCUGUCUACAAUAAGACACAGACUUUUGACAAGCAGGGAUUUCAUGCAGGGACGCCUCCACCUUUCAGCCUGCCCUCGGUCUUGGGCUCCACUGGGCCCCUGGCCUCGGGAGCGGCCCCUGGCUAUGCACCCCCACCAUUCCUACACAUCUUGCCAGCCCACCAGCAGCCCCACUCACAGCUGCUGCACCACCACCUUCCGCAGGAUGCACAGAGUGGCUCGGGUCAGCGCAGCCAGCCCAGCUCCCUGCAGCCCAAGUCUCAAGCCUCCAAACCUGCCUACGGCAACUCUCCAUACUGGACAAACUAAACCCAGAAGAGAGGGGUGGGCUGGGGCAAGGCUUAUCCUGGGCAGGAGAGAACACACGAGCACGUAUUUGGGAGCCCAGUGCCCUUUCCUAGAAUUCCCGACAUGUGUCAGCCAUGCCUCUGUGGGGAGUCUGCCUCCCAGACUGGCUACUGUAUGUAAUGUAUUUAUGUAUGUAUUUGUAAAUGUGAUAGAAGUCUGGGGGGGAGUUGGGGGAUGGCGGCAGAUGUUAGCCAGGUCUGCCCUCCCCAUUCAAGCCCCUUCUCCACUGUAGCAAAAUAAGCACCCCCACCCCAUCUGCCUUCAGGUCUUCUUCACAGCCUGCACUGCCCAGUGGGCCACUAGGGGCAGUCUCUGGAAGGGCUGGUUCAAGGCUGUUUGGGUAUAGGGGUCAGGUACCAAUGAAGAAUCACGACUUGUCUCACUCCUUUGGAAAUUGUUUUCUUUCCUGUGUAAUUACUUCAUACCUCUGUUUUUGAGAAACUGUUCCGUUUGUCAUCUGUCAUGGUCUCCUUCCACCAAAUCUUCAUCUGGGAAUAGCAGCGGUAUCCCUCCACCCAAGUAUGGCCACCUGUUUGUCUUCAUAUAGAACAGGGGCUUCUGGUCUGGUCAUGUCCCUAGAGACUUACUAGAGACUGGCUGACCAUGAAAAAAAAAAAAAUAAUCUGAGUUAUUCAGCCAGUCAGCUCCCCUUUAAAAAUCUAAGGUAUCUCCAAGCAACACAUCUCCAUUCUAGUUGUCUUGAACCACGUGGGCAACUGUUUCAGGGGUUUUCUCUUGCCCAAUCCCCACCUAAUAAAGUUCUGAGAGCAUG